AAGCAGUGUUCUCCAGCAGCCUGCCUGCUCCCACUCCCCUUCCCUGCCCCCCAUAACAAUGCAGAAAACAAAUAGACUGAACUUGGACCACUCCCCUUCCCCACCCCCAUAACAAUGCAGAAAACAAGUAGACUGAACCUGGAUUGAGAUUGGAAGGGAAGAUGUGAUGGAAAACUUGAGUAGGGGGUAGUGGGAAGUCAAGGAAUAGAGAGUGGUAAUGAGGCUGCUAAUUGAAGGGUUGAGCCAUAGGAAUCCUGCUUAUUAAGGAACAAAGCCAAGCCAAGACAAGGCUGGUAAAUGUGGAUAAUGAAGAGGAUGAAGAAUCUAAAUGAGUCAAGUGCAGGAUUAAUGGAAAUAAAAGAGUACUAGAGAUGGAAAAAUUGGCACAUAGAUGUGAGAAUUCUCAAUUUAAGAUUCUGGAGUUAGCAGUUUCAGGUGAUGAUAAGGGCCAAAGAAUGACCAAUGAUGGGUGGAUAGCCAAGAUUAAUAGUGCUAAUUAUAACAAUAUUAAUAUUAAUAAAAACUACUAUUCAUUGAACACUGUGUAGUAGUCACUAUAGUAAAUAUUUUCCAUAGGUUAUCAUGCUUAUGUUUCACAUAUUAGUAUCAACAUUUUACAGAUGAGGAAACUGGAGCUCAGUGAGAUUGAGUAACUUUUCCCAAGACUCACAGCUACGAAGUACCUGAGUCUUUCUGAGUCCUUCUAGCAUUGAAGCACUUAUGCCUGACUACUAAACCAUGCUAGCCUUCUGCAAAGUAGGGGUCAUUGAAGAAGAAGGCAAAGAGCAUUAAGUCUUGUGUGUUGGAAUCAAUUGUUCUUAUGGAUAAUGAAGUCCCCAGAAUAUAUAGCUUCUGUGUGGAAAGGAAGAUAGUCAUACGACAAAAUUCUCAGUAAAUGGAGAUGGCUGACUCAAAGGUCAGUAGGUGACAACUAUAAAUAUAGCUAUAAUGUAAUCUUAAAAGUGGAUAAAAUCGAAUAACAAUGACUUACAAGUCAUCUUGGGAAACUAGGAGAAUACUGACUUGUCUUCCUGGCCCCCAAAGUGAUGCAUAUGAAAAUAUUAACCAUUCAUUUCUUAACCCUCUCUUCUCUCUUGGCUUGUGAAAUUUUAUAUAUAUAUGUGUGUGUGUGUGUGUGUGUGUGUGUGUGUGUGUGUGUGUGUAUUUACAUAUGUUUGUGUAUAUAUACGUGUGUGUGUGUAUAUAUAUACACCUGUGUGCACACGCGCACACACACCCACAGACACACCCCCCUCUUUUUUGGUUUUCCUCGUACCCCUCUAACCACUCCUCUUCAGUCUCAUUGGCUGGAUUCUUCUUUGCCAGCUCCUUCAUGUUGGUGAGCCUCUGGAUUCUCUCCUCCUCCUCAUUUCUCUUUCUUUGUGCUUUCCUUUGAUGAUCUCAUCUAUUUCUAAGCUUUCAUAUACCACCUAUAUGUUAAUGACUUCUGAAUGUUCAUCUAGAGAUGAAUCUAGAACUUUCUUCAAAUCCCAACAUCCUUAUAUAGGAAGAUGUACCCAGAAGAAAUAGCCCAUGAUAUUUCAGGGCAAUAUCAUGUGACUAGAGAAAGUCAUCUUAGGCUAGUAAUCUCCACUCAUGCCCAUCUAGUUGAGGGCUCAAUUCACUUAUUUUCAACAUCCACAACCAUUUCUAAGGUGAUAGCUUCUCUGGUUACUUAUCACUGGUAUGACCAAACAUCUUGAUUUGCCUAAGAUGGCUCUGGUUUAUGCCUAUUGUUCAAGACCAACCUGGCCAACAUGGUGAAACCCCAUCUCUACUAAAAAUACAAAAAAUUAGCUAGGUGUGGUGACGCACACCUGUAAUCCCAGCUACUGAGGAGGCUGAGGCAUGAGAAUCGCUUGAACCUAGGAGGUGGAGGCUGCAGUGAGCCGAGAUCGCACCACUGCAUUCCAGCCUGGGCGACAAGAGUGAGAUUUCAUCUCAAAAAAAAAAAAAAAAAAAAAAUCAGUAUAUCCUGUGUAACUUGUAAGAGCUGCUUAUAUCCAUCAGCUCACUCUUAUCCUACUUUUCAUAUUUAAGUGUCUAGACUUCAUUGUACCUUUACUGCAUUAUGACUUAGAGUUUGUUCAAGAUUAAAAUCUUUUGCCAUUUCCUGAAUUUCUGCUUAGUGAUGCUUCCAAAGACAGUAAUACUGAUAAUUAGUCUUGAAAUAUUUCUCUAUUAGCCUUAUUUAAACAUUUUGGAGAAUGUUUCUAAAGUCAUUUGCUCCACAUUACUGAAAUAUAUUUAUUUUCUCUUCACCUUAUUUUUUAAAAAACAGAACCCAGUAAGGCAGUUUUGAUAAAACCUGAUUAUGCACAGUUUAAGGAAACAUUGAAGAUGUAUAAUUUUAAUCUUAAAUUAAUGUUGAUACUUACUACAUUUUCUGAAUGUUGUACUCUCAUAAAAGUUCACAACCCAAAGAGGCAUUUAGAGAUCAUCUAGUUUUUGUUUUUUAAAUAUCUGUAAGAAUAAUGGGCAUCAGAAAGGUUAAGCACCUUGCCUGAGAUCCUAAAGAGAACAAGGCAAAACAGAAAACUGAGAAUCUCUUGACUUUUAGUCUACUAUUCUUUCUGUUAUACUACCAACCAUUUGAAAAUUUUAAUGUAUUUUAAGAAAGUGAUCUCAUAACCAAAAGAUGUCUGUGCAUCAUAGAAACCCAUAGUGUUUGGUUUUCAAUAUGUAAUUUCCUUAUUUUACCCCUUUAACUUUAACCCUUUUUCUUUAUACAAGUCUACAUUUAGACCACAGUGAUAGAAACUACCGAGUAUGAUAGAAACUACCCAGUGUGGUAGGGAAAAAAAUUAUGUGGGUGGAAUUUGAAAUGCCUGUGCUCAGAAAAUAUUUAUAUAUAUUUCUUUCUUAUUUCUGUUCUGUGCUCUGCUCCCCUAACUAUCCAUCUUCACACAUGGUUAUAGAACAGUAGAUUCAGCCACCAGAUCUGAGUUUGAACUUGUGGUUAUCUUUCUUGGUGUGAAAUGUUUUAUAACAGUAAACACAUUUUUCUGUAAUUGACUGCCUCAAUUAUUGUUUUUUCUUUCUUUUGAAGGGAAGCUAAUUUUUUUGUUUCUUAAGAAUUAUGAAAUAAGAGGAAACGUGCUAUCUAUACGUGCAAGGUGUAUUUAAAGCUUAUAAAUAUCUGUGUUCAGUAUGUCUAAAACUUAUUUUGCAGAAUCUUCUAAAACUUAUUUUGCAGAAUCUUUAACCUUAUGCAAAAUAUAUAUGAAAAAAGUUUAUUAUUAUAGUACAGCUACAUAAAUUAUUUUUAUUAUUUUCAUUUCACAUUUAGGAUAAGGCUCCAAGCUGUUUUUAGCAUUCCUCAGGAGGUAUGGAAAACUAUCAUGCUUAUAAUUGAUUUUCAAGAACUUUUAAACUGUAUGCUUUGGAUUAUCUUUAACAGUAUGAAUAAGCAUCCAAAAUUUUAUUGCUGAAGGUUUUUGGUUUUAAUAUGAAAAAUGUUUGGUAAGGUUUUUAAGGUGUUUCGGUAGUGCCUUAAAUGCUAAUUGUGGAAUAGAGAGUGGCUUUUGUAAAUGUGUCUGUUUCUCAGAGCCUUACCUGGGGGAACAUUUCCUAAAGGUAUUUGAAUAUUAAAAUGUUUUCUAUCAAAGUUAGUAUUAAAUGAACUGGUGUUUAUUUAUUGAACUCUUGUAUCUGUGGUACUGUGUUAGAUGCUCAUAUUUUUCUGAUCAAAUAAGAUCUGGUUUCCUUUCUUAAGAAAAGUAUAAUCUAGUUUUAAAAGAAACAAUACAGUACAGUGUGGUGAGUGAUAAGAUAGAGGCAUAUGGAAAAGUAAUUAAUUGGGAAUUAAUGGGAAUUUCCAUAGCAACAUGAUAAAAAAUUAGUUGAGAAAGUGUAUACCCUUUGAAGGAAUUGCAGGGUGGUACAACGUGUUAUGUGUUGGGAGUUUGGAAAAGCUAAAUUGUAGCAGGUAUUGCAUACUUUGAUAAUAAGCAGUUGGGAUCUUCUUCCCUAUGAAUUGGAGUGACAUUUGUCAUUCCAAGGGAUAUGAGUAACAUUUUUAGUGGUAGCAUAUUUAGAUUAAACAGAAAAUAGACCAGACAGUGUGAUCAAGUAGGAGGUUGUUAGUAUUGCAAGUAAGAGAGGAGUUGAAGGUCUAAGGAUGCUUAGGUGUAAGAUUAGGGGGAAGGACCAGAUUCAAGGUGAUGAUGAUAAUAUCUAAUAAUAAUUGAUUUUCCUGCAAUCUGCCAGGCACUGUGCUAUGCAUUUUACAUGAAUUAUCUCGUUUAAUGUUGAUAUUCGCAACAACUACAGCUACUCUUAUGAACUCAGUUGUAUAGAUGAGAAACUGAGGCUUAGAAAGAGGAAGUCGAGUACCCAAGGUCAUAGAGCAGCAGAUGCAGAGGUGAACCAGUAAGUGGUCAAGAGGGAGAAUUGACUAGGCACUAGAUGAAGUGCUAUUCUGGUUUCUCACCUCAGUCACUGGGUAGAGGCCAUUUACUGAAAGAGGAAUGAAGAAGGAAGAGCUGGCUUAUUGGAGAGAGAAGUCAAUGUCUGCUUUGGAGAAUAGAAAUUUGUAUAUAGAAUACAAAGGGAUUGCAUGAGUCUGAAUCCUGGCCCUGACACUUAGUAACUCUGUGACUUUGAGCAAUGACCUAACCUUACUGUGCUUCAGUUUCCAAUAUGUGUCAACUAGGGAUAAUAAUGUUACUUAGGAGAUUGUUAGGAGGAUUAAACUAACUACUCUACUUACCUAGAGUGCUUACAAUAGUGCCUGAUGUGUAGUAAUUAAUCACUGUAGGUGUUAGCCAGAUUAUCAUCAUCAUCAUCAUGCUAUAAAAAUCCAAAGGUCUCUUUUGAGGAGGGAUGUAGUAGUCAGUGUAAAACAUCUAGCACAUUCCUUCUAACAGGGAUAGAAAGCCGGGGAGAUGAUUUACCUGGAUGAACCUUCAUAGUUCCUUUAAAUGCCGUCUCUCUCUCUAUAGCUACAAUAUCUCAGAAUUUCUACCCUUUUGCGGUGCUCAGGGCCAAACACAGGUUCUUCCUGAGAUAUCUGGUUGCCGAAUUUGUUUGUUUUUAGGAAAAAUGAACUACCUGUUGAAAGGCUUAAGUUUGGUGCGUUUUAGUGUGACUUCCUCUGAAUUUCUAUUAAAAUUUUGCCUGGCUGCCCUAUGCCUGAGUUUCCUUUAUUUCCUGGCCAGCUUUGUUCUGCAAGGAGCCAGAGUAACCUCUCCUCCCUAGGUCAGCGCCCCAGGUUUCAAGGCAGCCGGAAUGGCAUGUUAACCAAGAUUUCAUGGGCUUGGGGAGAGGGGUAGCGAAAUAGGCAAUGUUGUUUAUUGACACCCUGAAAUAUGAAAAAAUAAUAUGUACACCUUUCUGGGCCAUUGCUGUCUUAGAUUUCCAUUCUUCCCCCAGAACUACUGCCUUACUGCUGUUAUACAUGUUUUUUUUUUUAGUUUUCUUUACACAAUUCUACAUAAAUUGGAAAUAUUUCAUUAAACACAUUUUUCUACUUUAACUUAGCUUAAAUGCAUAAUACAGAAUAAAUAUAGGAACAGCACAACCAUUUAUUUCCAUAUUCACUAGUUAAGGAUUAUUAUAUUCCCACAUUUUAAAUAUAGAACAUCUAGUUCAGAGCCAAUUCUUAACCCUCCGAUGCUGAAAUUUCUGAUGCUCUUUAGAGCUGAAGGUGUUACUUCUUGUUAAAAUGUACAUACUUCUUUUCAAGAGGAGCAACAUUUUUCUUCCAAGUCAUUUACUUUUUGGUAUAAAUGUACAAUGUGGAAACAUGGAAAAAGAUAACAAAGCUGUAAAACAUCUUGAGAAGUUUGUGGGGGGGCAAGAAGUUUGUGGUGCUUGGAGGCGUGCCUGGGAGUUGGCACUAAGUACAGCUGUAAUUAGUCAGUUUUCUGUCCUGUCCACACAGAAAACCGUCUAGUUACAGUUGUAAGUUGUGCCAGACCUAAUCGCUAAAAUGCUCUGAAAGGUAGAAUUCUGAAAGAUAUAGUUUGGUUGUGAGUAGUCUGUCAAAAAUUGUAUGCAGUAUUAGGAAAAACAUUGGAUAGGACUCUGCAGACCUAGCUGUUAAGUCCUCUGACUUUUGGGAAAUCUCUUAACUGCUGUCUGCCUUAGUUUAUCUGUAAAAUUUUGAGGGAGGUGAUAUGGUCAUUAACCCAGAGAUCGUUUAACUCUCUGAAAGUUGAUUGUAGAAUGGAUUCUCAUUUUAAAAUAAUUUAUUAAAUGCGAACUCUGGCAGUUUUCCUUUAUUGUCAAUCAACUUGUCACUUACCUCAGUAUUAGUUGAAAAAAUGUCUUUUGAGUAUGGCAGUUACGUCUUACAUAUGACUGUGUUCCAGAGGCUCAUUUCUAAGAUGGUUGUUGAGAAUGUUUAGAAUGCAUAAGAUUUGCCCUUACAGACAAAAUAAACUACAGUAUACUUGAGUGUUGCAUUGUGAGACUUCCCCGGGAAAAAGGUCCGGCAAAGUGCUGAGAUUACCUCAACAUGUCUAACUGGCUUACUGUUUGCCUUACGUGGUACUAUCCUACUUUUGGGGCCCUUUCCCCAGAUUGUUGGAGCUACCACAAAUGGCUUUGAGGUACAGGAAUCUCUUCUCCCUCCCUGACAGGCAGGGGGCUGGGGGAGAAUGGGGCAAAACAUAUUGCUAGCAAUUCAAGUUGGAACUCUGAAUUCAUUUUCCCAUUGAGGCAUGAGUUGUUACUAAGAUUCUGUAGGGUCUGUAGUUAAAAGCCUUAACAGCAUUUCCUUCCUGAAGCUGUCCCAAUGUUAGUAUCUACGGAACUGGAGACCACAAUCUUUAUUUCCUAAGAAUACAUGACAUCUUGACUUCUAGUCAGAUGCUCCUUAAUGCACUCUUCAGAGAAGCAAGUUCAGUAUUUGUCAAGAAGGGCCUGGGCGCUAAACAACUGCUAUCAUUUCUUUUAAAGUUAAUAGAUUCAAUGAAAGUUGAACAUACCACGAAGUAUGGUGAAGCUUUGUUCUAAGAAUAUUUGUUUCAUCUAGUUUAUGAGUCCAAAUGAUAUAGACUGUAAAUGUCACAGCAGUGGUGAAAGACUGCUCGGUCAUGAGCACCGACAGUAACUCACUGGCACGUGAAUUUCUGACCGAUGUCAACCGGCUUUGCAAUGCAGUGGUCCAGAGGGUGGAGGCCAGGGAGGAAGAAGAGGAGGAGACGCACAUGGCAACCCUUGGACAGUACCUUGUCCAUGGUCGAGGAUUUCUAUUACUUACCAAGCUAAAUUCUAUAAUUGAUCAGGCAUUGACAUGUAGAGAAGAACUCCUGACUCUUCUUCUGUCUCUCCUUCCACUGGUAUGGAAGAUACCUGUCCAAGAAGAAAAGGCAACAGAUUUUAACCUACCGCUCUCAGCAGAUAUAAUCCUGACCAAAGAAAAGAACUCAAGUUCACAAAGAUCCACUCAGGAAAAAUUACAUUUAGAAGGAAGUGCCCUGUCUAGUCAGGUUUCUGCAAAAGUAAAUGUUUUUCGAAAAAGCAGACGACAGCGUAAAAUUACCCAUCGCUAUUCUGUAAGAGAUGCAAGAAAGACACAGCUCUCCACCUCAGAUUCAGAAGCCAAUUCAGAUGAAAAAGGCAUAGCAAUGAAUAAGCAUAGAAGGCCCCAUCUGCUGCAUCAUUUUUUAACAUCGUUUCCUAAACAAGACCACCCCAAAGCUAAACUUGACCGCUUAGCAACCAAAGAACAGACUCCUCCAGAUGCUAUGGCUUUGGAAAAUUCCAGAGAGAUUAUUCCAAGACAGGGGUCAAACACUGACAUUUUAAGUGAGCCAGCUGCCUUGUCUGUUAUCAGUAACAUGAACAAUUCUCCAUUUGACUUAUGUCAUGUUUUGUUAUCUUUAUUAGAAAAAGUUUGUAAGUUUGACGUUACCUUGAAUCAUAAUUCUCCUUUAGCAGCCAGUGUAGUGCCCACACUAACUGAAUUCCUAGCAGGCUUUGGGGACUGCUGCAGUCUGAGCGACAACUUGGAGAGUCGAGUAGUUUCUGCAGGUUGGACCGAAGAACCGGUGGCUUUGAUUCAAAGGAUGCUCUUUCGAACAGUGUUGCAUCUUCUGUCAGUAGAUGUUAGUACUGCAGAGAUGAUGCCAGAAAAUCUUAGGAAAAAUUUAACUGAAUUGCUUAGAGCAGCUUUAAAAAUUAGAAUAUGCCUAGAAAAGCAGCCUGACCCUUUUGCACCAAGACAAAAGAAAACACUGCAGGAGGUUCAGGAAGAUUUUGUGUUUUCAAAGUAUCGUCAUAGAGCCCUUCUUUUACCUGAGCUUUUGGAAGGAGUUCUUCAGAUUCUGAUCUGUUGUCUUCAAAGUGCAGCUUCAAAUCCCUUCUACUUCAGUCAAGCCAUGGAUUUGGUUCAAGAAUUCAUUCAGCAUCAUGGAUUUAAUUUAUUUGAAACAGCAGUUCUUCAAAUGGAAUGGCUGGUUUUAAGAGAUGGAGUUCCUCCCGAGGCCUCAGAGCAUUUGAAAGCCCUAAUAAAUAGUGUGAUGAAAAUAAUGAGCACUGUCAAAAAAGUGAAAUCAGAGCAACUUCAUCAUUCGAUGUGUACAAGAAAAAGGCACAGACGAUGUGAAUAUUCUCAUUUUAUGCAUCAUCACCGAGAUCUCUCAGGUCUUCUGGUUUCGGCUUUUAAAAACCAGGUUUCCAAAAACCCAUUUGAAGAGACUGCAGAUGGAGAUGUUUAUUAUCCUGAGCGGUGCUGUUGCAUUGCAGUGUGUGCCCAUCAGUGCUUGCGCUUACUACAGCAGGCUUCCUUGAGCAGCACUUGUGUCCAGAUCCUAUCGGGUGUUCAUAACAUUGGAAUAUGCUGUUGUAUGGAUCCCAAAUCUGUAAUCAUUCCUUUGCUCCAUGCUUUUAAAUUGCCAGCACUGAAAAAUUUUCAGCAGCAUAUAUUGAAUAUCCUUAACAAACUUAUUUUGGAUCAGUUAGGAGGAGCAGAGAUAUCACCAAAAAUUAAAAAAGCAGCUUGUAAUAUUUGUACUGUUGACUCUGACCAACUAGCCCAAUUAGAAGAGACACUGCAGGGAAACUUAUGUGAUGCUGAACUCUCCUCAAGUUUAUCCAGUCCUUCUUACAGAUUUCAAGGGAUCCUGCCCAGCAGUGGAUCUGAAGAUUUGUUGUGGAAAUGGGAUGCUUUAAAGGCUUAUCAGAACUUUGUUUUUGAAGAAGACAGAUUACAUAGUAUACAGAUUGCAAAUCACAUUUGCAAUUUAAUCCAGAAAGGCAAUAUAGUUGUUCAGUGGAAAUUAUAUAAUUACAUAUUUAAUCCUGUGCUCCAAAGAGGAGUUGAAUUAGCACAUCAUUGUCAACACCUAAGCGUUACUUCAGCUCAAAGUCAUGUAUGUAGCCAUCAUAACCAGUGCUUGCCUCAGGACGUGCUUCAGAUUUAUGUAAAAACUCUGCCUAUCCUGCUUAAAUCCAGGGUAAUAAGAGAUUUGUUUUUGAGUUGUAAUGGAGUAAGUCAAAUAAUCGAAUUAAAUUGCUUAAAUGGUAUUCGAAGUCAUUCUCUAAAAGCAUUUGAAACUCUGAUAAUCAGCCUAGGGGAGCAACAGAAAGAUGCCUCAGUUCCAGAUAUUGAUGGGAUAGACAUUGAACAGAAGGAGUUGUCCUCUGUACAUGUGGGUACUUCUUUUCAUCAUCAGCAAGCUUAUUCAGAUUCUCCUCAGAGUCUCAGCAAAUUUUAUGCUGGCCUCAAAGAAGCUUAUCCAAAGAGACGGAAGACUGUUAACCAAGAUGUUCAUAUCAACACAAUAAACCUAUUCCUCUGUGUGGCUUUUUUAUGCGUAAGUAAAGAAGCAGAGUCUGACAGGGAGUCGGCCAAUGACUCAGAAGAUACUUCUGGCUAUGACAGCACAGCCAGCGAGCCUUUAAGUCAUAUGCUGCCAUGUAUAUCUCUCGAGAGCCUUGUCUUGCCUUCUCCUGAACAUAUGCACCAAGCAGCAGACAUUUGGUCUAUGUGUCGUUGGAUCUACAUGUUGAGUUCAGUGUUCCAGAAACAGUUUUAUAGGCUUGGUGGUUUCCGAGUAUGCCAUAAGUUAAUAUUUAUGAUAAUACAGAAACUGUUCAGAAGUCACAAAGAGGAGCAAGGAAAAAAGGAGGGAGAUACAAGUGUAAAUGAAAACCAGGAUUUAAACAGAAUUUCUCAACCUAAGAGAACUAUGAAGGAAGAUUUAUUAUCUUUGGCUAUAAAAAGUGACCCCAUACCAUCAGAACUAGGUAGUCUAAAAAAGAGUGCUGACAGUUUAGGUAAAUUAGAGUUACAGCAUAUUUCUUCCAUAAAUGUGGAAGAAGUUUCAGCUACUGAAGCCGCUCCCGAGGAAGCAAAGCUAUUUACAAGUCAAGAAAGUGAGACCUCACUUCAAAGUAUACGACUUUUGGAAGCCCUUCUGGCCAUUUGUCUUCAUGGUGCCAGAACUAGUCAACAGAAGAUGGAAUUGGAGUUACCUAAUCAGAACUUGUCUGUGGAAAGUAUAUUAUUUGAAAUGAGGGACCAUCUUUCCCAGUCAAAGGUGAUUGAAACACAACUAGCAAAGCCUUUAUUUGAUGCCCUGCUUCGAGUUGCCCUCGGGAAUUAUUCAGCAGAUUUUGAACAUAAUGAUGCUAUGACUGAGAAGAGUCAUCAAUCUGCAGAAGAAUUGUCAUCCCAGCCUGGUGAUUUUUCAGAAGAAGCUGAGGAUUCUCAGUGUUGUAGUUUUAAACUUUUAGUUGAAGAAGAAGGUUACGAAGCAGAUAGUGAAAGCAAUCCUGAAGAUGGCGAAACCCAGGAUGAUGGGGUAGACUUAAAGUCUGAAACAGAAGGUUUCAGUGCAUCAAGCAGUCCAAAUGACUUACUCGAAAACCUCACUCAAGGGGAAAUAAUUUAUCCUGAGAUUUGUAUGCUGGAAUUAAAUUUGCUUUCUGCUAGUAAAGCCAAACUUGAUGUGCUUGCCCAUGUAUUUGAGAGUUUUUUGAAAAUUAUUAGGCAGAAAGAAAAGAAUGUUUUUCUGCUCAUGCAACAGGGAACUGUGAAAAAUCUUUUAGGAGGGUUCUUGAGUAUUUUAACACAGGAUGAUUCUGAUUUUCAAGCAUGCCAGAGAGUAUUGGUGGAUCUUUUGGUAUCUUUGAUGAGUUCAAGAACAUGUUCAGAAGAGCUAACCCUUCUUUUGAGAAUAUUUCUGGAGAAAUCUCCUUGUACAAAAAUUCUUCUUCUGGGUAUUCUGAAAAUUAUUGAAAGUGAUACUACUAUGAGCCCUUCACAGUAUCUAACCUUCCCUUUACUGCACGCUCCAAAUUUAAGCAACGGUGUUUCAUCACAAAAGUAUCCUGGGAUUUUAAACAGUAAGGCCAUGGGUUUAUUGAGAAGAGCACGAGUUUCACGGAGCAAGAAAGAGGCUGAUAGAGAGAGUUUUCCCCAUCGGCUGCUUUCAUCUUGGCACAUAGCCCCAGUCCACCUGCCGUUGCUGGGGCAAAACUGCUGGCCACACCUAUCAGAAGGUUUCAGUGUUUCCCUGUGGUUUAAUGUGGAGUGUAUCCAUGAAGCUGAGAGUACUACAGAAAAAGGAAAGAAGAUAAAGAAAAGAAACAAAUCAUUAAUUUUACCAGAUAGCAGUUUUGAUGGUACAGAGAGCGACAGACCAGAAGGUGCAGAGUACAUAAAUCCUGGUGAAAGACUCAUAGAAGAAGGAUGUAUUCAUAUAAUUUCACUGGGAUCCAAAGCGUUGAUGAUCCAAGUGUGGGCUGAUCCCCACAAUGCCACUCUUAUCUUUCGUGUGUGCAUGGAUUCAAAUGAUGACAUGAAAGCUGUUUUACUAGCACAGGUUGAAUCACAGGAGAAUAUUUUCCUCCCAAGCAAAUGGCAACAUUUAGUACUCACCUACUUACAGCAGCCCCAAGGGAAAAGGAGGAUUCAUGGGAAAAUCUCCAUAUGGGUCUCUGGACAGAGGAAGCCUGAUGUUACUUUGGAUUUUAUGCUUCCAAGAAAAACAAGUUUGUCAUCUGAUAGCAAUAAAACAUUUUGCAUGAUUGGCCAUUGUUUAUCAUCCCAAGAAGAGUUUUUGCAGUUGGCUGGAAAAUGGGACCUGGGAAAUUUGCUUCUCUUCAACGGAGCUAAGGUUGGUUCACAAGAGGCCUUUUAUCUGUAUGCUUGUGGACCCAACCAUACAUCUGUAAUGCCAUGUAAGUAUGGCAAGCCAGUCAAUGACUACUCCAAAUAUAUUAAUAAAGAAAUUUUGCGAUGUGAACAAAUCAGAGAACUUUUUAUGACCAAGAAAGAUGUGGAUAUUGGUCUCUUAAUUGAAAGUCUUUCAGUUGUUUAUACAACUUACUGUCCUGCUCAGUAUACCAUCUAUGAACCAGUGAUUAGACUUAAAGGUCAAAUGAAAACCCAACUCUCUCAAAGACCCUUCAGCUCAAAAGAAGUUCAGAGCAUCUUAUUAGAACCUCAUCAUCUAAAGAAUCUCCAACCUACUGAAUAUAAAACUAUUCAAGGCAUUCUGCACGAAAUUGGUGGAACUGGCAUAUUUGUUUUUCUCUUUGCCAGGGUUGUUGAACUCAGUAGCUGUGAAGAAACUCAAGCAUUAGCACUGCGAGUUAUACUCUCAUUAAUUAAAUACAACCAACAAAGAGUACAUGAAUUAGAAAAUUGUAAUGGACUUUCUAUGAUUCAUCAGGUGUUGAUCAAACAAAAAUGCAUUGUUGGGUUUUACAUUUUGAAGACCCUUCUUGAAGGAUGCUGUGGUGAAGAUAUUAUUUAUAUGAAUGAGAAUGGAGAGUUUAAGUUGGAUGUAGACUCUAAUGCUAUAAUCCAAGAUGUUAAGCUGUUAGAGGAACUAUUGCUUGACUGGAAGAUAUGGAGUAAAGCAGAGCAAGGUGUUUGGGAAACUUUGCUAGCAGCUCUAGAAGUCCUCAUCAGAGCAGAUCACCACCAGCAGAUGUUUAAUAUUAAGCAGUUAUUGAAAGCUCAAGUGGUUCAUCACUUUCUACUGACUUGUCAGGUUUUGCAGGAAUACAAAGAGGGGCAACUCACACCCAUGCCCCGAGAGGUUUGUAGAUCAUUUGUGAAAAUUAUAGCAGAAGUCCUUGGAUCUCCUCCAGAUUUGGAAUUAUUGACAAUUAUCUUCAAUUUCCUUUUAGCAGUUCACCCUCCUACUAAUACUUACGUUUGUCACAAUCCCACGAACUUCUACUUUUCUUUGCACAUAGAUGGCAAGAUCUUUCAGGAGAAAGUGCGGUCAAUCAUGUACCUGAGGCAUUCCAGCAGUGGAGGAAGGUCCCUUAUGAGCCCUGGAUUUAUGGUAAUAAGCCCAUCUGGUUUUACUGCUUCACCAUAUGAAGGAGAGAAUUCCUCUAAUAUUAUUCCACAACAGAUGGCCGCCCAUAUGCUGCGUUCUAGAAGCCUACCAGCAUUCCCUACUUCUUCACUACUAACGCAAUCACAAAAACUGACUGGAAGUUUGGGUUGUAGUAUCGACAGGUUACAAAAUAUUGCAGAUACUUAUGUUGCCACCCAAUCAAAGAAACAAAAUUCUUUGGGGAGUUCCGACACACUGAAAAAAGGCAAAGAGGACGCAUUCAUCAGUAGCUGUGAGUCUGCAAAAACUGUUUGUGAAAUGGAAGCUGUCCUCUCAGCCCAGGUCUCUGUCAGUGAUGUCCCAAAGGGAGUGCUGGGAUUUCCAGUGGUCAAAGCAGAUCAUAAACAGUUGGGAGCAGAACCCAGGUCAGAAGAUGACAGUCCUGGGGAUGAGUCCUGCCCACGCCGACCUGAUUACCUAAAGGGAUUGGCCUCCUUCCAGCGAAGCCACAGCACUAUUGCAAGCCUUGGGCUAGCUUUUCCUUCACAGAACGGAUCUGCAGCUGUUGGCCGUUGGCCAAGUCUUGUUGAUAGAAACACUGAUGAUUGGGAAAACUUUGCCUAUUCUCUUGGUUAUGAGCCAAAUUACAACCGAACUGCAAGUGCUCACAGUGUAACUGAAGACUGUUUGGUACCUAUAUGCUGUGGAUUAUAUGAACUCCUAAGUGGGGUUCUUCUUAUCCUGCCUGAUGUUUUGCUUGAAGAUGUGAUGGACAAGCUUAUUCAAGCAGAUACACUUUUGGUCCUCGUUAACCACCCAUCACCAGCUAUACAACAAGGUGUUAUUAAACUAUUAGAUGCAUAUUUUGCUAGAGCAUCUAAGGAACAAAAAGAUAAAUUUCUGAAGAAUCGUGGAUUUUCCUUGCUAGCCAACCAGUUGUAUCUUCAUCGAGGAACUCAAGAAUUGUUAGAAUGCUUCAUCGAAAUGUUCUUUGGUCGACAUAUUGGCCUUGAUGAAGAAUUUGAUCUGGAAGAUGUGAGAAACAUGGGAUUGUUUCAGAAGUGGUCUGUCAUUCCUAUUCUGGGACUAAUAGAGACCUCUCUAUAUGACAACAUACUCUUGCAUAAUGCUCUUUUACUUCUUCUCCAAAUUUUAAAUUCUUGUUCUAAGGUAGCAGAUAUGUUGCUGGAUAAUGGUCUACUCUAUGUGUUAUGUAAUACAGUAGCAGCCCUGAAUGGAUUAGAAAAGAACAUUCCCAUGAGUGAAUAUAAAUUGCUUGCUUGUGAUAUACAGCAACUUUUCAUAGCAGUUACAAUUCAUGCUUGCAGUUCCUCAGGCUCACAAUAUUUUAGGGUUAUUGAAGACCUUAUUGUAAUGCUUGGAUAUCUUCAAAAUAGCAAAAACAAGAGGACACAAAAUAUGGCUGUUGCACUACAGCUUAGAGUUCUCCAGGCUGCUAUGGAAUUUAUAAGGACCACCGCAAAUCAUGACUCUGAAAACCUCACAGAUUCACUCCAGUCACCUUCUGCUCCCCAUCAUGCAGUAGUUCAAAAGCGGAAAAGCAUUGCUGGUUCAAUUCCAAUGAAGGGUUCCAUUAUUCCUCAUCUACCAAGACAUCAUUUUGGUUCCUAUGGUCAACUUCCGAUGCCCUUCUCCUUCGGUCCAUUAAAUCAAGACUCAUCCCCCCAGUUUUCUCCUGGAUGCACUACCUGUGUUGUACCUCCUGGAGCAGGUCCUCGAAAAUUUCCCCUUGCUCAAACUGAAUCGCUUCUGAUGAAAAUGCGUUCAGUGGCAAAUGAUGAGCUUCAUGUGAUGAUGCAACGGAGAAUGAGCCAAGAGAACCCUAGCCAAGCAACUGAAACGGAACUUGCGCAGAGACUACAGAGGCUCACUGUUUUAGCAGUCAACAGGAUUAUUUAUCAAGAAUUUAAUUCAGACAUUAUUGACAUUUUGAGAACUCCAGAAAAUGUAACUCAAAGCAAGACCUCAGUUUUCCAGACCGAAAUUUCUGAGGAAAAUAUUCAUCAUGAACAGUCUUCUGUUUUCAAUCCAUUUCAGAAAGAAAUUUUUACAUAUCUGGUAGAAGGAUUCAAAGUAUCUAUUGGUUCAAGUAAAGCCAGUGGUUCCAAGCAGCAAUGGACUAAAAUUCUGUGGUCUUGUAAGGAGACCUUCCGAAUGCAGCUUGGGAGACUACUAGUGCAUAUUUUGUCGCCAGCCCACGCUGCACAAGAGAGAAAGCAAAUUUUUGAAAUAGUUCAUGAACCAAAUCAUCAGGAAAUACUACGAGACUGUCUCAGCCCAUCCCUACAACAUGGAGCCAAGUUAGUUUUGUAUUUGUCAGAGUUGAUACAUAAUCACCAAGGUGAAUUGACUGAAGAAGAGCUAGGCACAGCAGAACUGCUUAUGAAUGCUUUGAAGUUAUGUGGUCACAAGUGCAUCCCUCCCAGUGCAUCAACAAAAGCAGACCUUAUUAAAAUGAUCAAAGAGGAACAAAAGAAAUAUGAAACUGAAGAAGGAGUGAAUAAAGCUGCUUGGCAGAAAACAGUUAACAAUAAUCAACAAAGUCUCUUUCAGCGUCUGGAUUCAAAAUCAAAGGAUAUAUCUAAAAUAGCUGCAGAUAUCACCCAGGCAGUGUCUCUCUCCCAAGGAAAUGAGAGAAAAAAGGUGAUCCAGCAUAUUAGAGGAAUGUAUAAAGUAGAUUUGAGUGCCAGCAGACAUUGGCAGGAACUUAUUCAGCAGCUGACACAUGAUAGAGCAGUAUGGUAUGACCCCAUCUACUAUCCAACCUCAUGGCAGUUGGAUCCAACAGAAGGGCCAAAUCGAGAGAGGAGACGUUUACAGAGAUGUUAUUUAACUAUUCCAAAUAAGUAUCUCCUUAGGGAUAGACAGAAAUCAGAAGAUGUUGUCAAACCACCACUCUCUUACCUGUUUGAAGACAAAACUCAUUCUUCUUUCUCUUCUACUGUCAAAGACAAAGCUGCAAGUGAAUCUAUAAGAGUGAAUCGAAGAUGCAUCAGUGUUGCACCAUCUAGAGAGACAGCUGGUGAAUUGUUACUAGGUAAAUGUGGAAUGUAUUUUGUGGAAGAUAAUGCUUCUGAUACAGUUGAAAGUUCGAGCCUUCAGGGAGAGUUGGAACCAGCAUCAUUUUCCUGGACAUAUGAAGAAAUUAAAGAAGUUCACAAGCGUUGGUGGCAAUUGAGAGAUAAUGCUGUAGAAAUCUUUCUAACAAAUGGCAGAACACUCCUGUUGGCAUUUGAUAACACCAAGGUUCGUGAUGAUGUAUACCACAAUAUACUCACAAAUAACCUCCCUAAUCUUCUGGAAUAUGGUAACAUCACCGCUCUGACAAAUUUAUGGUAUACUGGGCAAAUUACUAAUUUUGAAUAUUUGACUCACUUAAACAAACAUGCUGGCCGAUCCUUCAAUGAUCUCAUGCAGUAUCCUGUGUUCCCAUUUAUACUUGCUGACUACGUUAGUGAGACACUUGACCUCAAUGAUCUGUUGAUAUACAGAAAUCUCUCUAAACCUAUAGCUGUUCAGUAUAAAGAAAAAGAAGAUCGUUAUGUGGACACAUACAAGUACUUGGAGGAAGAGUACCGCAAAGGAGCCAGAGAAGAUGACCCCAUGCCUCCCGUGCAGCCCUAUCACUAUGGCUCCCACUAUUCCAAUAGCGGCACUGUGCUUCACUUCCUGGUCAGGAUGCCUCCUUUCACUAAAAUGUUUUUAGCCUAUCAAGAUCAAAGUUUUGACAUUCCAGACAGAACUUUUCAUUCUACAAAUACAACUUGGCGACUCUCAUCUUUUGAAUCUAUGACUGAUGUGAAAGAACUUAUCCCAGAGUUUUUCUAUCUUCCAGAGUUCCUAGUUAACCGUGAAGGUUUUGAUUUUGGUGUGCGUCAGAAUGGUGAACGGGUUAAUCACGUCAACCUUCCCCCUUGGGCGCGUAAUGAUCCUCGUCUUUUUAUCCUCAUCCAUCGGCAGGCUCUAGAGUCUGACUACGUGUCGCAGAACAUCUGUCAGUGGAUUGACUUGGUGUUUGGGUAUAAGCAAAAGGGGAAGGCUUCUGUUCAAGCGAUCAAUGUUUUUCAUCCUGCUACAUAUUUUGGAAUGGAUGUCUCUGCAGUUGAAGAUCCAGUUCAGAGACGAGCGCUAGAAACCAUGAUAAAAACCUACGGGCAGACUCCCCGUCAGCUGUUCCACAUGGCCCAUGUGAGCAGACCUGGAGCCAAGCUCAAUAUUGAAGGAGAGCUUCCAGCUGCUGUGGGGUUGCUAGUGCAGUUUGCUUUCAGGGAGACCCGAGAACAGGUCAAAGAAAUCACCUAUCCGAGUCCUUUGUCAUGGAUAAAAGGCUUGAAAUGGGGGGAAUACGUGGGUUCCCCCAGUGCUCCAGUACCUGUGGUCUGCUUCAGCCAGCCCCACGGAGAAAGAUUUGGCUCUCUCCAGGCUCUGCCCACCAGAGCAAUCUGUGGUUUGUCACGGAAUUUCUGUCUUCUGAUGACAUAUAGCAAGGAACAAGGUGUGAGAAGCAUGAACAGUACGGACAUUCAGUGGUCAGCCAUCCUGAGCUGGGGAUAUGCUGAUAAUAUUUUAAGGUUGAAGAGUAAACAAAGUGAGCCUCCAGUAAACUUUAUUCAAAGUUCACAACAGUACCAGGUGACUAGUUGUGCUUGGGUGCCUGACAGUUGCCAGCUGUUUACUGGAAGCAAAUGCGGUGUCAUCACAGCCUACACAAACAGAUUUACAAGCAGCACGCCAUCAGAAAUAGAAAUGGAGACUCAAAUACAUCUCUAUGGUCACACAGAAGAGAUAACCAGCUUAUUUGUUUGCAAACCAUACAGUAUACUGAUAAGUGUGAGCAGAGACGGAACCUGCAUCAUAUGGGAUUUAAACAGGUUAUGCUAUGUACAAAGUCUGGCGGGACACAAAAGCCCUGUCACAGCUGUCUCUGCCAGUGAAACCUCAGGUGAUAUUGCUACUGUGUGUGAUUCAGCUGGCGGAGGCAGUGACCUCAGACUCUGGACGGUGAACGGGGAUCUCGUUGGACAUGUCCACUGCAGGGAGAUCAUCUGUUCCGUGGCUUUCUCCAACCAGCCUGAGGGAGUAUCUAUCAAUGUAAUCGCUGGGGGAUUAGAAAAUGGAAUUGUAAGGUUAUGGAGCACAUGGGACUUAAAGCCUGUGAGAGAAAUUACAUUUCCCAAAUCAAAUAAGCCCAUCAUCAGCCUUACAUUUUCUUGUGAUGGCCACCAUUUGUACACAGCAAACAGUGAUGGGACCGUGAUUGCCUGGUGUCGGAAGGACCAGCAGCGCUUGAAACAGCCAAUGUUCUAUUCCUUCCUUAGCAGCUAUGCAGCCGGGUGAAUGCGAAUGAACUUCACGUUCUCCAAAGCACUUUAACUCCAAACUAGAUUUGUUGACUUCACCAGUUUUAGGAGGUUGAACCUAAAGAAAUGGAUGACUGGACAAACCAUCCAAAUAAUGAUAAAGUCUAUUCAUCUGCACAAAAUUCUGAAGAGUCACAUGAUCCUAAGAGGAAAGUUCUGUUCUAUUUUAGUGAUAAUCUGGAAGAUUGUGUCAAUAUGCACUAGCCAACAAGUUUUAAGCCUCGCAUGGUACAUUAAAAUGAUAUUCUUAAAAUUUUUUCCCACCAAGGUAUUCCAAAGAAAAUAUUAAGGUCUCCCCUUUUUCUAUGAUUCCAAAAGGACCAGUAGAAUUUAAAUUGGUUGGUUGAUUGUUUAUAUAAAACACACUAAAAUUAUAUUUUAAAAGUUUACUGCCAUGAAAUACUCCUCCCACCACACACACAUGCUCCAAAAGAGGAAAGAAAAAAAGAUAAUUUUUAGGACUUGAUAAUUGCUUUCUUUGAGAAGCAAAUUAUUCAGUAGGUGCCUCUGUACCAAAUAUUUUAUGGAAUAUCUAAAUACUAAAAUAAACUAUGAAUGAAUCUCAAAAUUAGGCAGUUUUUGCCAGUUGCUUUCUUAGCUCAAAGGAGAACCAGAAUUUUUUUGACAGCCACAAACAAGAAUACAGGUAUCUUGGAUUUCAGACACAUUCUGUUUCUUCAUAAAAAUUUUACUUAAAAUCUGUAACGCUAGAUAUUGACUAUCCUUAGUUGAGUCACUGAGGUUUAAACACAAUGGUAAGUCUUAAAGUCUGCUAUUUACAGAGCAUUGAAUCUGUACCAAUUUGCAAUAGAAAGCCUUCAGUAUGCAAGAAGUUUGCAUGGGUAUUAAGAACACAGCCUAAAUAAGGCAUUUGAUCUAAUCUGCAGGAAGAAUUUUCUUCCCCAAAACAGAAUUAUAAAAGCUUACUUUAAACAGGAGGCAGAAUAAUUCUUUUAGGAAACCAUUUCAUUCUGUUUCUACUAACCUAUACCAUCUGAGAAUUCUAGGAAGAAUAAUAAAAUCUCGUGUAUUCCACAGCAAACUUACAUACCAUAAAGACAGAAUUCCUAAACAUCUUGGAGCCGUCUGUCUCUCCCAUAUGAUGGCUGUCUGUAUAUUUUUACUUGGGGUGCUGCUUUAUUGGCUUUGAAAACACUGUCAGAUAAGCUCAGUAAUAUGUUACCAUGGGAUAAAAAUAUGUAUCCCUGCCUAAGAAUAACUUGUGCAUUUGUUAUGGAAAUUUAAUUCAUAUGGUGUUUACAGUACUACUUUUGUAACUUCCAGACUUUCUAAAACAUUCUGCUUAAAAACCAUAUAAAAUAUAAUUCCAAAGUCUCUGCUGUCAAGAUAGAUUCGAGAGAAAGCACGUGGCCAUGUAUGCUUUAACCUUAAACUGCAUACACAUGUAGUGAUACCUAGGCUGCAUUUAGAUCACCGUGUGCUCAGGCCAGGUGUGAAUCCUGAGGUCCAUGGAGGUGCAGAGAUGAGAUUACUCCUAUUCACGUUGAAGUGAUUUGCUUUGUUAACAAAAAAUUGCAGCUAUUGUCUAGCUUUCAUUUUUUUACUGAGAACUUUAAAUUAGUCCCCUAUUAGAAUAGGGUUGCUACUCAUCUUUUUUUAAAAACCGAAUUUCAUCAUUUAUCUAAAGAGAAAAUAUGCAGAAUAACUGGUCUUGUUAAGAGUGCAAUAUUAUAUUUUUAUGUAAAAAUAAAAAUUAAUUUGGGGGGAUUAUUUAUUCAGCAUGAAACCUAAUAUGUAUAUGUUUGAAAUACUUCAUAAUGUGCAUGUUGUAGCAAACAUUUCUGUAAAUUAUCACAAGCUCUGUUACCUUUAUAUACACUGCCUCUUCAAUUUGGAAAUAAAUUUCAUAAAAAUAGAUGUAAACA